AAUAUUUGUGCAGGCGCCGCAGGAACGGGCUCCGCGGACGACGGGCUCCAGGGACGCACAGGCAGCGGGCCUCCCACCGCGGGUGCCGGGGGCGGGGGGGCUGCCCCCAUGCGGGGCCCUUCCUGGUCGCGGCCUCGGCCGCUGCUGCUGCUGUUGCUGCUGCUGUCGCCUUGGCCUGUCUGGGCCCAGGUGUCGGCCACGGCCUCGCCCUCGGGGUCCCUGGGCGCCCCGGACUGCCCCGAGGUGUGCACGUGCGUGCCGGGAGGCCUGGCCAGCUGCUCGGCACUCUCGCUGCCCGCCGUGCCCCCGGGCCUGAGCCUGCGCCUGCGCGCGCUGCUGCUGGACCACAACCGCGUCCGUGCGCUGCCGCCAGGUGCCUUCGCGGGAGCGGGCGCGCUACAGCGCCUGGACCUGCGCGAGAACGGGCUGCACUCGGUGCAUGUGCGAGCCUUCUGGGGCCUGGGCGCGCUGCAGCUGCUGGACCUGAGCGCCAACCAGCUGGAAGCACUGGCACCAGGGACUUUCGCGCCGCUGCGCGCGCUGCGCAACCUCUCAUUGGCCGGCAACCGGCUGGCGCGCCUGGAGCCCGCGGCGCUAGGCGCGCUCCCGCUGCUGCGCUCACUCAGCCUGCAGGACAACGAGCUGGCGGCACUCGCGCCGGGGCUGCUGGGCCGCCUGCCCGCUCUAGACGCGCUGCACCUGCGCGGCAACCCUUGGGGCUGCGGGUGCGCGCUGCGCCCGCUCUGCGCCUGGCUGCGCCGGCACCCGCUGCCCGCGUCAGAGGCCGAGACGGUGCUCUGCGUGUGGCCGGGACGCCUGACGCUCAGCCCCCUGACUGCCUUUUCCGACGCCGCCUUUAGCCAUUGCGCGCAGCCGCUCGCCCUGCGGGACCUGGCCGUGGUUUACACGCUCGGGCCGGCCUCCUUCCUCGUCAGCCUGGCUUCCUGCCUGGCGCUGGGCUCUGGGCUCACCGCCUGCCGUGCGCGCCGCCGCCGCCUCCGCACCGCCGCCCUCCGCCCGCCGAGACCGCCAGACCCGAACCCCGAUCCCGACCCCCACGGCUGUGCCUCGCCCGCGGACCCGGGGAGCCCCGCCGCUGCCGCCCAAGCCUGAGCGGCCGCGGCCGCCUGGAGCGCUCGAAGCUUCCCCCAUGCCUUUGCCCUCCCUUUACACUGUCUGCCGGCGUCAACAAGCGACACAGACCGAAAA